GCCCUCUUCCACCCCACGCUGCCCUGCCCAGGGCGAGGGCAGAGCGGGCCCGCCCAGGUGCGCCCGGGGGUUGGGCCGGAGUCCGGAAGGUGCGCCGCGCCGCCCCGAACCUGUCCCCUAGGCCUCCCCCCGCGUGAAAGUGAAAGUGUCGGACCCGCGGAGGUCAAGGAUAGGGGGGCGGGGCCAGCGCGGAGCUGGGAGCGGGAGCCGGGCACUCCAGGGGCCAUGGAUGGGCUCGGCCGCCGCCUUCGAGCCAGCCUGAGACUGAAGCGCGGCCAUGGGGGGCACUGGAGAUUAAAUGAGAUGCCUUAUAUGAAACAUGAGUUUGAUGGAGGACCACCCCAGGACAAUUCAGGGGAAGCUUUAAAGGAACCAGAAAGGGCCCAGGAGCACUCUUUGCCCAACUUUGCUGGGGGGCAGCACUUCUUUGAAUACCUUCUUGUGGUUUCUCUCAAAAAGAAGCGUUCAGAGGAUGAUUACGAGCCUAUAAUCACCUACCAAUUUCCCAAGCGGGAGAACCUGCUUCGGGGUCAGCAGGAGGAGGAGGAGCGGCUGCUCAAAGCUAUCCCCUUGUUCUGCUUCCCAGAUGGGAAUGAGUGGGCAUCACUCACCGAGUAUCCCAGGGAGACCUUCUCCUUCGUUCUGACCAAUGUGGAUGGGAGCAGAAAGAUUGGAUACUGCAGGCGCCUCUUGCCUGCCGGCCCUGGCCCUCGCCUUCCCAAAGUGUACUGCAUCAUCAGCUGCAUCGGCUGCUUCGGCUUGUUCUCCAAGAUCCUGGAUGAAGUGGAGAAGAGACAUCAGAUCUCCAUGGCUGUCAUCUACCCGUUCAUGCAGGGCCUCCGAGAGGCAGCCUUCCCUGCUCCUGGGAAGACUGUCACUCUCAAGAGCUUCAUCCCCGACUCAGGCACUGAGUUCAUUUCACUGACACGGCCCCUGGACUCCCACCUAGAACAUGUGGAUUUUAGUUCUCUAUUGCACUGUCUCAGUUUUGAACAGAUACUUCAGAUCUUUGCCUCUGCCGUGCUGGAGAGAAAAAUCAUCUUCCUGGCGGAAGGUCUCAGCACCUUGUCUCAGUGCAUCCAUGCUGCUGCCGCACUGCUCUACCCCUUCAGCUGGGCGCACACCUACAUCCCUGUUGUCCCUGAGAGCCUUCUGGCCACCGUCUGCUGCCCCACCCCCUUCAUGGUUGGAGUACAAAUGCGCUUCCAGCAGGAGGUCAUGGACAGCCCUAUGGAAGAGGUCCUGCUGGUCAAUCUUUGUGAAGGAACCUUCUUAAUGUCGGUUGGUGAUGAAAAAGACAUCCUGCCACCGAAGCUUCAGGAUGACAUCUUAGACUCUCUUGGUCAGGGGAUCAAUGAGUUAAAGACUGCAGAACAAAUCAACGAGCAUGUUUCAGGCCCCUUUGUGCAGUUCUUUGUCAAGAUUGUGGGCCAUUAUGCUUCCUAUAUCAAGCGGGAGGCAAAUGGGCAAGGCCACUUCCAAGAAAGAUCCUUCUGUAAGGCUCUGACCUCCAAGACCAACCGCCGAUUUGUGAAGAAGUUUGUGAAGACACAGCUCUUCUCACUUUUCAUCCAGGAAGCCGAGAAGAGCAAGAAUCCUCCUGCAGGCUAUUUCCAACAGAAAAUACUUGAAUAUGAGGAACAGAAGAAACAGAAGAAACCAAGGGAAAAAACUGUGAAAUAAGAGCUGUGGUGAAUAAGAAUGACUAGAGCUACACACCAUUUCUGGACUUCAGCCCCUGCCAGUGUGGCAGGAUCAGCAAAACUGUCAGCUCCCAAAAUCCAUAUCCUCACUCUGAGUCUUGGUAUCCAGGUAUUGCUUCAAACUGGUGUCUGAGAUUUGGAUCCCUGGUAUUGAUUUCUCAGGACUUUGGAGGGCUCUGACACCAUGCUCACAGAACUGGGCUCAGAGCUCCAUUUUUUGCAGAGGUGACACAGGUAGGAAACAGUAGUACAUGUGUUGUAGACACUUGGUUAGAAGCUGCUGCAACUGCCCUCUCCCAUCAUUAUAACAUCUUCAACACAGAACACACUUUGUGGUCGAAAGGCUCAGCCUCUCUACAUGAAGUCUGUGGACAUGUAAGGACGAGAGUAAAGAGGAAAAUCUUAUUUUUAUAUGUGUCUUUGGCUUUUACUAUGGGUAAAAGUAUUUUCCUCGUGGAAAAUAAGGCAAUGAAUAUGACAAUCAAGUGGACUACAAGUGGAAGACCUGGCCAUGGGGAUAUGUUUGGAGUGAUAGAAUCAUGGGGGGCAGCAGCUCUACUUCUUCUAACCGGAAGGGUAAGAGAUACUGGUAAAAGCAGCAGCAGCACUGGACACAGGGCAUCUAAGUCCUUGGUUUGGAGUCAGGUGUGCUUUCCAGAAUCCUGGGAGGAGAGGCUGCUCACUGAAGGGAAGCAGCUUCAGUCUAGAGUAAUUUGAGGAUAGGAAUUUCAGUCAACAGCAGCCUGUGAAGAACACUACAUGGCUUCCAUACGUAGGUCUGUUUCCCCAUCACUUUCAGUUUGCACUAGUCCUUUACCUUCAGUCUUGGACAUCCUACCUCCAACUGAUCUUUAUUUUGAGCAGCACAGUCCAAUUCUUUAACUAAAGGUGAAGGGAUCGCUGCACUGACGUUCUUCCCCUUUGAGAAAAGAAUCGUAAUUUUAAGAGUCUGAAGGAGUUUAGUGGUCACCUAGUCUCUCCUCCCUUGAUACCUCUACUGAUACUUUCUACUCAAGCAUUGGGAAGCUUUUUUAGAAGAAUCUUAUCUUCAAAAAUUCUACCUUUUUUAAUGUGUGUAUUUGUGGCCCUCAGAAGUUCCUAAAUUCUAUACAAAGAACACAAAAGUUUCUGGAGGGUGGAACCGGGCAUACUGAAGUUCAAGCCAAUGUAAUUUGCUUUUGGGAGUGCAGAGACCUACUGCAGGUGGCAGAUGUCCCACUGUCCACACACCGUGCUUAGCUACACUACUAUUCUUCACAGCUUCUAGGAAUUACAUUUUUUUUUGGUAGUUUAUGGCAGUGGUGCCUAAAUAUAGUUGUACCUCCAAAGGUUUCAGAACAGGAACUGGAAUCCUGAGAAUCUUGUGAAAAUAUCCUCUUAUGCCUCAUCACAAAUACACCAAAUCAUCUCUAGUGAUAGGACCUGGAAAUCUGUACUUUCUUAAAAGGUUCUUCAGGUAAGGUUUGCUGAGGUUUAUUACAAAUGUACCCUUGAUUUGAUGCUAAUGCUGUAUUUAGGGCUGAAGGAAGCACACACUAAAUAUCUGAGUGCUUUUCAGAUUCCAUCUAUGCUGAAAAAGAAUCUAGGAGAAUAAACACAUUUCAAUUAGCCCUUAA